GGGACGGAGCGAUGUCGGGCCGAGGCGCGGGCGGGUUCCCGCUGCCCCCGCUAAGCCCUGGCGGCGGCGCCGUGGCUGCGGCCCUGGGAGCGCCGCCUCCCCCCGCGGGACCCGGCAUGCUGCCCGGACCGGCGCUCCGGGGACCGGGUCCGGCAGGAGGCGUGGGGGGCCCCGGGGCCGCCGCCUUCCGCCCCAUGGGCCCCGCGGGCCCCGCGGCGCAGUACCAGCGACCUGGCAUGUCACCAGGGAACCGGAUGCCCAUGGCUGGCUUGCAGGUGGGACCCCCUGCUGGCUCCCCAUUUGGUGCAGCAGCUCCGCUUCGACCUGGCAUGCCACCCACCAUGAUGGAUCCAUUCCGAAAACGCCUGCUUGUGCCCCAGGCGCAGCCUCCCAUGCCUGCCCAGCGCCGGGGGUUAAAGAGGAGGAAGAUGGCAGAUAAGGUUCUACCUCAGCGAAUCCGGGAGCUUGUUCCAGAGUCUCAGGCGUACAUGGAUCUCUUGGCUUUUGAGCGGAAGCUGGACCAGACCAUUGCUCGCAAGCGGAUGGAGAUCCAGGAGGCCAUCAAAAAGCCUCUGACACAAAAGCGAAAGCUUCGGAUCUACAUUUCCAAUACGUUCAGUCCCAGCAAGGCGGAAGGCGAUAGUGCAGGAACUGCAGGGACCCCUGGGGGAACCCCAGCAGGGGACAAGGUGGCUUCCUGGGAACUCCGAGUGGAAGGAAAACUGCUGGAUGAUCCUAGCAAACAGAAGAGGAAGUUUUCUUCAUUCUUUAAGAGCCUCGUCAUUGAGCUGGACAAGGAGCUGUACGGGCCUGACAAUCACCUGGUGGAGUGGCACCGGAUGCCCACCACCCAGGAGACAGAUGGCUUCCAAGUAAAACGGCCUGGAGACCUCAACGUCAAGUGCACCCUCCUGCUCAUGCUGGAUCAUCAGCCUCCCCAGUACAAAUUGGACCCCCGAUUGGCAAGGCUGCUGGGAGUGCACACGCAGACGAGGGCCGCCAUCAUGCAGGCCCUGUGGCUUUACAUCAAGCACAACCAGCUGCAGGAUGGGCACGAGCGGGAGUACAUCAACUGCAACCGUUACUUCCGCCAGAUCUUCAGUUGUGGCCGACUCCGUUUCUCCGAGAUUCCCAUGAAGCUGGCAGGGUUGCUGCAGCAUCCAGACCCCAUUGUCAUCAACCAUGUCAUUAGUGUCGACCCUAACGACCAGAAGAAGACAGCCUGUUACGACAUCGAUGUGGAGGUGGACGACCCACUGAAGGCCCAAAUGAGCAAUUUUCUGGCCUCUACCACCAAUCAGCAGGAGAUCGCCUCCCUUGAUGUCAAGAUCCAUGAGACCAUUGAGUCCAUCAACCAGCUGAAGACCCAGAGAGAUUUCAUGCUCAGUUUUAGCACCGACCCCCAGGACUUCAUCCAGGAAUGGCUCCGUUCCCAGCGCCGAGACCUCAAGAUCAUCACUGAUGUGAUUGGAAAUCCUGAGGAGGAGAGACGAGCUGCUUUCUACCACCAGCCCUGGGCCCAGGAAGCAGUAGGCAGGCACAUCUUUGCCAAGGUGCAGCAGCGAAGGCAGGAACUGGAACAGGUGCUGGGAAUUCGCCUGACCUAACUGCUCAGGGAUCUUUCUUCCCAGCCCUGGAGCCUGGAGGGAGACCACCCUCUGGGUCCUUGCUGGGGCCGCAGACACGUAGGCUGGGGUGAGGAGUGUCUGCUGUCACCCUCUACUCUCCAGCUUUAGUCUUAUAAAUGUAGUGAUAGGAUUCCUUGUUGCUUGGUCCCCAAAGCCUUAUACUUUUUGCAUUGGCUUUAAUUGGGUUCAGCAGAUGCCUCCUCUGCCCCCCUGCAGGCAGGCCCAAGUAGGACUGCUGGAGGCUGUGCUUUGACAUUGUAAGACAUUUCCGAACCAAAGGCUGCUGGGUUUGCAUGUUUACAGACUCCCCCUGGGGCGAGGGUCAGAGCUGGCUCUGGGGAGCUGGGCUAGGAAGAGGAGGUGCAGCCCAGACUCUUCCUAGCCUUUCUAAACCAAAGUUCUUUGCCAUUCCUACAAGCCCAGCCUUGCUGCUGGUUUUUUCCUUUCCUUUGGGUAUUUGCACUAUUUUGGGAGCAAGUUUUCUAUGUGGGAGCCACUUUUUUUGUACAGGGGUAAGUUGGGGGUUUUCAGGGAGCCUGUUAGGUGCCUCCUUCUUUUCUUUCCUCAAUCUAUGCAAGCGGCUCUGGCCGCCAUCAUCUCCUGGGAUGCCAGAGGGCUGCCUCUCCAGCGGCUUGGGCCGGGGAGGGGACACUCCAGUUCUCUAGCAUGGCCUGAGGUAUGGGGUAUGUGCAUGUGGAGGCCAGGGUAAGGUGAAUGGGGAGGCUGGGAGGACUGGUGUUGCCCUUUGGAGCUUGGUGAGGAGGGUGGGCCUAGGGCUUGGCGAGUGCCACAUCUGGCAGGUUUGGAAAUUUCCAAAUAAAUCCUUUUGUCUAUUG